AGGAUUUUUUUUAAAAAGCACUGAUUACUAAAGGGAACUCUUAUUGUAUUAAAUCCUCAGAGUGAGAUAAUAACUGAAUCUCUUCCGCAACUCCUUCUCAGUUGAAUGGUGGGGGAAAUUUAAUGUGGUCCUGAGAGGCCCCAAAUCAUUUACCAUCCCAGCUCUACCUUUGAUGUGGCAGUCUCUCCUGGGAUCAUUUUCUGGGUGCAGAUGCUCACAGGGCGCAGUUUGACUCCUUCUGCAGUUCUCUGUGCAGAACUAAGUUAAGCCUAAGUUUGGCCUUUGUCACUUGCAAUGAUAAGAGACCAGCUUUGGUCUAUGGGGUGCAGGCUGGUGUCAGCACAGACUAGAGGCUUUGGGUUUGUUUAGAACAAACUGUAAUUAACAUAGGGCACAAUAUAGUCUUUCAGGAAUUAGCUGUCUAAGAGGCUGGAGUGGAGCAGAGCCUCUGCUUCCAGGAACAAUGCCCAUUGGGGAUGCUUGGGAUGGUCUUUCAACAGAGGCCAAUUGAUUGACUGAUGUACCUCUUGCCUUGAAGCUUGGCAUGUAUACAGGCACCACAGAAGAGAGACAAUCCCUGCCAAUCUCAUUUGGGAUCGGUAAUUUGAAACAGGAGAAAGCAAAAUGGGUUGGGUGGCCCAGACCCCUUGGACUAUGUUAGCAUGUACAGGAAUGUGGGGAGCCCUUCUGCUAACAUCCCCGAGCACUGGCACUACAUCAGCUUCGGCCUGAGUGAUCUCUAUGGUGACAACAGAGUCCAUGAGUUUACAGGAACAGAUGGACCUAGUGGUUUUGGCUUUGAGUUGACCUUUCGUCUGAAGAGAGAAACUGGGGAGUCUGCCCCACCAACAUGGCCCGCAGAGUUAAUGCAGGGCUUGGCACGAUACGUGUUCCAGUCAGAGAACACCUUCUGCAGUGGGGACCAUGUGUCCUGGCACAGCCCUUUGGAUAACAGUGAGUCAAGAAUUCAGCACAUGCUGCUGACAGAGGACCCACAGAUGCAGCCCGUGCAGACACCCUUUGGGGUAGUUACCUUCCUCCAGAUCGUUGGUGUCUGCACUGAAGAGCUACACUCAGCCCAGCAGUGGAACGGGCAGGGCAUCCUGGAGCUGCUGCGGACAGUGCCUAUUGCUGGCGGCCCCUGGCUGAUAACUGACAUGCGGAGGGGAGAGACCAUAUUUGAGAUCGAUCCACACCUGCAACAGGAGAGAGUUGACAAAGGCAUCGAGACAGAUGGCUCCAACCUGAGUGGUGUCAGUGCCAAGUGUGCCUGGGAUGACCUGAGCCGGCCCCCCGAGGAUGACGAGGACAGCCGGAGCAUCUGCAUCGGCACACAGCCCCGGCGACUCUCUGGCAAAGACACAGAGCAGAUCCGGGAGACCCUGAGGAGAGGACUCGAGAUCAACAGCAAACCUGUCCUUCCACCAAUCAACCCUCAGCGGCAGAAUGGCCUCGCCCACGACCGGGCCCCGAGCCGCAAAGACAGCCUGGAAAGUGACAGCUCCACGGCCAUCAUUCCCCAUGAGCUGAUUCGCACGCGGCAGCUUGAGAGCGUACAUCUGAAAUUCAACCAGGAGUCCGGAGCCCUCAUUCCUCUCUGCCUAAGGGGCAGGCUCCUGCAUGGACGGCACUUUACAUAUAAAAGUAUCACAGGUGACAUGGCCAUCACGUUUGUCUCCACGGGAGUGGAAGGCGCCUUUGCCACUGAGGAGCAUCCUUACGCGGCUCAUGGACCCUGGUUACAAAGACCUCCGUCCUGUGAGCUCCCGAGCCGUCCUGUGUGCUCACCUUCCUGUGUGCACUCCUUCCUUGUUAUCUCACAGCGUGGAAACUUUUGUUCUUGGCAGCUGACAAUUCCCAGGGGAAACCUGAUUCUGUUGACCGAAGAGUUUGUAGAGAAAAUGUUGGAGGAUUUAGAAGAUUUGACUUCUCCAGAGGAAUUCAAACUUCCCAAAGAGUACAGCUGGCCUGAAAAGAAGCUGAAGGUCUCCAUCCUGCCUGACGUGGUGUUCGACAGUCCGCUACACUAGCCUGGGCUGGGCCCUGCAGUGGCCAGCAGGGAGCCCAGCUGCUCCCCAGUGACUUCCAGUGUAACAGUUGUGUCAACGAGAUCUCCACAAAUAAAAGGACAAGUGUGAGGAAGACUGCGCAGUGCCACCCCGCAGCCCAGUGGGGUGCCAUGCACAGGCCACAGGCCCUCCACCUCACCUCCAGCUCAGGGGCCGCACCCCGCCGCUGGCUAAGCCUUGUGACCCAUCAGGCCAGUGAGUGGGCAAAUGCGGACCCUCCCUGCCUGCAGCCUGCACAGAUUCUGGUUUGAGGUUUGACUCUGGACCCUGGCUGUGCCCCUAGGUGGAGACAGCCCUCUUUCUCACCUACCCCCUGCCGCACAGCCCAGCAGGAGGGAGGCGGACAGCCAGAUGCAGAGCGAGUGGAUGCACUUCCCAGCUCAUCUCUGGAAGCCUUUGCUACUCAAGCUCCUCUGGCCGCGGAACAAUUCCUCUGAUCAUGUUUGGUUUUCUUCUUCCUUAUUUUAUUUUGUAGAAACCGGGUGGUAUUUUAUUGCUCUGCAAAGAUGUCCAGAAGCCAUGUAUAUAAUGUUUUUUAAACAGAACUUCAUUCCCCGUUGAACUUUCGCAUUCUCUGACAGAGGCCUAGGGCUGUAUCUCUCCCUGGGCUGCCACCAGAGAAGGUGCUUGGUGUUCGCCUGCCAGCCCAGAGCCCUGGAGGAGCCGGCUGCACAGAGAGGCUUUUCUUCCCAGCUGGGCCUGGUGGAGCCCGGGGCAGGGGGAGAGUAGAGACACUCCCUUGUGCAGCUUUGAGCCUAGUUUAGCUGGGGCCAGGGAGGGGUGCUACUGUUUUCCAAGUGAAUGGGUCUCAAAGACUUGGUGACCCCAGCCUCAUCUUCUAGGCCUUUUCCACCCAACCAGGCCUACCUGGGAGAGGGUGAGGUUCAGCACAUCACACACCAUCCCCACUGUCAUUCAGGGCCUGGGUCUCCAGCUCUGUAACCAGUCCUGUCCCAUUUCCUCAGUCCCUGGGCCUCCCAGCCUUCAGGCUGUAGGGCUGCCUUACUAAAAUUGAAAAAUCCACCUCUUAACAUCUCUUUCACUUUGGUUUUGCUAACACUGCUCUCUGCUGCCCUCCCAUCCUCCCUGUAUCCAUUCAUGCCCUAUCUUUCAUUCUCCACUCCUAAUCCCUCUCCUUUCUGGCAUCCUGGCCUCUCGUGGUCCUCAGCCCCUCACCCCCAGUACUGCAGAUCUCACAGUUUGCCUUCCAGAAGCCAGCCUAUCUCUAGCCCAUGGUUUUGGAGUUCCUCUCGGGUUAUCUCCCACGCCUGACCUGGAACCAGCAAGCCCCUUUCCUGCCUUCUUACCCCCAACUCUAGGGAUGGGACUGUUACAAUACUUCAAGAUCACUCUUUACACCUCUUCAAAGCAAAGUCAUGACAAUGCAGGGCUCCUCAUUGCUCCCAUCUGCCUCUGCUGCACACACAGGCACCAGCAGGGAUGCCACAGGAGUGCCCACAGGGUGCAGGACUCCACUGAUGAGAGAUCCAGCCAAAGAGCUGCCCCCAGGGGUAUGAGGGCACCAGCUGGGUUCUCCAGGGAGCAGGAGUUGGACCUCCAUGGAGCCACUAGGCCUGGCCUCCUCUACACAUCCCCAGGGCUAUCUGGUUAAUUCCAUCAAGCUCAGAGUUAAAAGGCAUAUCAGCCUGGAGUAUUUGGGAGAGACUGGCUGCAGAUCCCCGCCAGCCAAGAUGCAAGCCACUCGGGACCUGAUGUCGGCAGCUGUGCCUCUACUGCCCUGAGGACUUACCAGAGGGAGCCCUACUGGCCUUCCCCCACCACAGCAGCCCUGCCUGUGAAGCUCUUGUUUCUGACAUUUCACAGGCAGAGAGGUGCCAUCAGUUCGCCUCCAUUCCUUGCCACCAUGACCAGCCUCUCCCUGAACUCUCUCUUGCUCGGGACCUGCCUGAGGGCUCCCUGCUGCAGUUCGCCGUACUUCCAUCUGCUGGGUGCCUCCAUCGUUGGUUGGGUGGGGAUGGGGCAUUUUCUGAGCUAAGCUUUGUCAUUAGUUUGUGAAGCACCUGGUCAGCAACCUGCCCCAGACCUGGAGGGUCUUUGUGGACUGAAGGUAGACACCAGCCAGCAUGGUGGCCCUGUUCUGGGGGAGCAGGGUAAGGCAGGAGGAAGUGGGUGAGCUCCGAGAUGAUGAGCACAUGAAGCCUGUGGCCCCUUCGUACCUGCAAUAUGUCAGGAGCCUCACGCUCACCCAAGAUCCUGCAGGGGCCAGGCUCCAUCUCACUGGCUCUGAGGGCAGGACAGGGUAUCACACAUUUCUCACCAGGCCUCCUUUCCUAUGGGCAUUGGUGCCUCCCAGAGGUUUCUUGGGCUGCUGGCUGGUGAGAGAGGACCCUUAAAGAAGAUCAAGCCAAGCUGACCUUGGACCCUGUCCAGCACAGCUUCUGGCACAGGAUGCUUGGUGAAUGUACCCUUUCUUUCCCUCCCUGCAGCUCUGAGGGAGCCCCUGACCUUGUAGUGGGUGGAGGAGGUAAGGGGCCUCCCUCCCUAAAUCUGCCUCUUCUGCAAGCUACUUGGAGACUUGCCUAGUUGUACCCACCCCUCCAGGUCCCUGGUGCUAGAGCUUCUGAGAAGGGCCUUUCCCUUUCCUCUUUGCCUGCUAUAUAAGGCAGGCUCCUGUGGCUCUGCUGGCUCAGUGUGGGCUGCAGGAGGACUGCAGACUCAGCUGCAAUUCUGAGGGGGGUUUGGGAGGCUUGUGCGAGGUCUCAGGCCUGUGUGGGGAGCUGGUGCCUCUUCCUGCCCGUAUCUUUCUCUUCCAAGGGCAGUGCUCCAAGGCAGGGACUGGAGAAGCCAAGGGGAGAGUCUAAAAGGGCUAGAGCAUUUUUAAAAAUAGACACAGGGUCUUGGGACUGGGGUUUCGGAUUGAGUUGCAAGCAGGGAGAAAACCUGAAGGUCGGUGCCCCUAUGGGGCUGACCAGUAGAGAAUUUCCUUUACUGUAUUUUUGUGUCUGGUCUUCCCUUUCUGGCUUCUAGGACAUCCAUGCCAGGUGAGGUGCCUGGGUCCCUGUUACAAGUCAGGAGCCCUGUAGGGAGACCCCUCCUUUUGUACAAGUACCUGAAUGCUGCGACAAGCAGAUUUUUGUAAAAUUUUAUAUUAGUUUUUAAUGUCAGUGGCGACUCGGUUCCUGGGGCUGCAGCCAGCCUGGGACUUUUGUAAGAAUUUUUGGGUGACUCACUUAGAUGUCGUUUCCUUCUUGCCCCCUCUUCCUCUCUGUAAUCUAAGUGCAUUAAACAUCUUUGCAGAAGUGCCUGGGUUGUGUGCUCAUUUCUGGCUGCCUGAAGUAGUGGAGCCGGAAGCCCGGGGCCCUGGCAGAGGGAGUGGGUUG